ACCCACCCCAGCCGCGACUGUCUCCGCCGAGCCCCCGGGGCCAGGUGUCCCGGGCGCGCCCCGAUGCGGCCGCGGCUGUGGCUCCUCCUGGCCGCGCAGCUGACAGUUCUCCAUGGCAACUCAGUCCUCCAGCAGACCCCUGCAUACAUAAAGGUGCAAACCAACAAGAUGGUGAUGCUGUCCUGCGAGGCUAAAAUCUCCCUCAGUAACAUGUGCAUCUACUGGCUGAGACAGCGCCAGGCCCCGAGCAGUGAUAGUCACCACGAGUUCCUGACCCUCUGGGAUUCCGCAAAAGGGACUAUCCACGGUGAAGAGGUGGAACAGGAGAAGAUAGCUGUGUUUCGGGAUGCAAGCCGGUUCAUUCUCAAUCUCACAAGCGUGAAGCCGGAGGACAGUGGCAUCUACUUCUGCAUGAUCGUCGGGAGCCCCGAGCUGACCUUCGGGAAGGGAACUCAGCUGAGUGUGGUUGAUUUCCUUCCCACCACUGCCCAGCCCACCAAGAAGUCCACCCUCAAGAAGAGAGUGUGCCGGUUACCCAGGCCAGAGACCCAGAAGGGCCCACUUUGUAGCCCCGUCACCCUUGGCCUGCUGGUGGCUGGCGUCCUGGUUCUGCUGGUUUCCCUGGGAGUGGCCAUGCACCUGUGCUGCCGGCGGAGGAGAGCCCGGCUUCGUUUCAUGAAACAGAAAUUCAAUAUCGUUUGCCUGAAAAUAAGUGGUUUCACAACUUGCUGUUGUUUUCAGAUUUUACAAAUGAGCAGAGAAUACGGUUUUGGUGUCCUGCUACAAAAAGACAUCGGUCAGUAACGAGCACGAUGUGGAAAAAUGAGAGAAGGGACACAUUCAACCCUGGAGAGUUCAAUGGCUGCUGAAGCUGCCUGCUUUUCACUGCUGCAAGGCCUUUCUGUGUGUGACGUGCAUGGGAGCAACUUGUUUGUGGGUCAUCGGGAAUACUAGGGAGAAGGUUUCAUUGCCCCCAGGGCACUUCACAGAGUGUGCUGGAGGACUGAGUAAGAAAUGCUGCCCAUGCCACCGCUUCCGGCUCCUGUGCUUUCCCUGAGCUGGGACCUUUAGUGGUGGCCGUUUAGCCACCAUCUUUGCAAGUUGCUUUGCCCUGGUAGGGCAGUAACAUUGGGUCCUGGGUCUUUCAUGGGGUGAUGCUGGGCUGGCUCCCUCUUGGUCUUCCCAGGCUGGGGCUGACCUUCCUCGCAGAGAGGCCAGGUGCAGGUUGGGAAUGAGGCUUGCUGAGAGGGGCUGUCCAGUUCCCAGAAGCCAUGUCAGUCUCUGAGGGCUUCCUUUGGGGCCGGGAACUUGCGGGUUUGAGGAUAGGAGUUCACUUCAUCUUCUUAGCUCCAAUUUCUACUCUUAAGUUUCUCAGCUCCCAUUUCUACUCUCCCAUGGCUUAAUGCUUCUUUCAUUUUCUGUUUGUUUUAUACAAAUGUCUUAGUUGUACAAAUAAAGUCCCAGGUUAAAGAUAACAAACGGGUCCUGUGACAUAAACGUACGAAAGCCCAUCUACAGCAAAGACAUCAGUGCUCAGUGGAACAGAAACCAGAAGGAGAAAAUUUGUACAUCCUCCUUUUGCACCUGAGAUCCUCAUUUGCCCGACAUUGUAGGUGUGGAGAGUCCUAGAGAGGCUAGGAAGCGCCCAGGGCACCCAGAGCCAGGCUGCAGGUGCCUCAGGCCCCUCUCCCAGCCCACUCCCAAGCUGAACUAGCACGUGUUCAUUUCUACCGCGGGUUGAACCGCAGGGAUCCCUGGCUUCAAGUCAGGCACCAAACAGAAGGUAGGAGGCAUGAGGGGUUCUGUCACAUGUCUCUUCAUUUUCUUAUUGAUUCUUAGCCUUGACAGUUGGAGAAGGAAAAAGCAAGGAGAAAGUGCUGAGCAGGAGUGGAGAGUGAAGAGCAGGACCUCGUGCCUGGGUUUGAAAAAGUGCCUGAGACCCAUCUUAGCCGCCCCUACCUGAGCUUUAGCAGCCUAGGAGCUAUUGCACCAUAAAACACUGCAACCUGAGGCUGCAUUAACAGAAGCACCACGUCCAGGUCCAGGGAGAAUCCAGCCUCACCUGCUUCUCCUGGCCAGCUCAAGGAAGGACAUUGACAAAUCAGGUUAUGUUCAGUUACCUGUGACAACCACAGAAUGUAAGAAAUGUUACAAAAAAAACAGGAAAGGAAAGACGACUCUGGGGAAGGGGCAGUGGGACCUUCUCCUGGCAUCUGGGGUGCGGCCGCAGCAGAAUGAGGUGUGGUGGGUGGAGUUAGAAAGGCAUAGAUGCAGUGUUACCGGAAGGAGGGCCUUGAGUGUAAGUUGUCCAGGUCCUUGGCAUUUUGAACAAAGAACUGAACAAAACAUACAAAGUAAUAAAGGAAUAAACGCAGCAAAAGGAAGAAUUUAUUGAAGUGAGAAAGCACUCCACAUGGUAGGAGUGGACCCUAAGCAGAUAGCCCAUGGGCCCAAUUGCAAAGUUUUCUGGGUUUUAAGUACCCCUUUUGAGGUACCUGUCGGCUACCCCUUAAUCUGGGUGAAGGAUUUGGUCCAUGGCUAAUGAAAGGCUGAGGUGAAUUGACGCCCUAUGCGGAUGAAGGGAUGGCCCGUGCUUGGUCUGUGGUCAAUCCAGGGCAGUCUCCCUUUCCAUCUGAGAUGCAGUGGAAGGGGGAGGGUUGUAGGGAGAGUAGCCUUUGAUCCUUGGUUACUCAGUGUGGGGAGAUGGGGUUUUUCCUUUUGGUGUACGUUAAUUGGCCUUAGAUGCCCUGCCCCCAGACCCAGGUGUUUUCCGUUUGCUCCAGCUUUGAGAAGUCAGCACAAAUUGGCCUCAGAUUCCCUGCCCCCAGACGUAGGUGUUUCUCCUUCAUUCAGCACGAAUUGGCCUUAGAUGCCCUGCCCCCAGACCCAGGUGUUUUCCAUUUGAUCCAGCUUUGAGAAGUCAGCACAAAUUGGCCUCAGAUUCCCUGCCCCCAGACAUAGAUGUUUCUCCUUGAUUCAGCACGAAUUGGCCUUAGAUUCCCUGGCCCCAGACCCUAGACUCCUGCCUCAGCAAGAGUUGUUCAAAAGAAACAAAAGCUCUGCCCAUCAGCUCUGAGGACAAGGGACAGGCUGCCUUCCAAGGCUGAGGGGAGGGGUGAAAGAAUUGGGGUCAGCUGGACCAGACUCCUCUAGGGUUCGUGUUUCAGGUGGGCCCCUCACCCGGCCCAUCACAAACAAAUAAGAGAUUAAGGCCUGCAGUGCACGUGGUCUGCCCUCCUUGAAGGCUCACACCCAGUGCACAGCGGAAGUAAGAACAGGCCACAAGGCCCCUUGUCCCACUGCAGGCUUUGAAAUUUGACCAUCUCCCUGCUGCUGUCUUUGCAAUUGCAUGUACUUGUUCACAAGUUCUCAUGGGGUUGGGCUGGGGGCAGGGGUGGUUUGUGCUCCUCCGUCAGUUUUCUGUGCAGCAGGCACCUGCCGAGGCGGGCUCAGCUCCGGCCACCCAGGGAGCUGGAGCAGGCUGGGCUGCCAAUGGUGGGGGCUGCAGUGAGAAGGUCUGCACCCAGCACCUGACCUUUGUUUGAAGAAGGAACUGAGCUGCUACUACACUCUAUAGGGCCAUUAUGAUGAAAUAUGCCCCCCAAACUCCAUCCAGCUAUCUUUUGACUAGCAGUUCCACUUGUUGGCAUUUAUCUGAAAGAAAUACAUCAAAAAGUGGCAUGCACAAAGAAAUACGCAUCAGAUUGUUCCUUCUAGUGCUGCUUACUAGCUAAAAAUGGGAAAUAAUCCAAAUGUCCAUCAAAAGGGACUGGUCAGAUAAAUUCAGACACAGUCUAAUAAGGGGGUUUAGGCGGCUGCUAAGGAAUGAGCUAGAUCCAUAUAUGCUGAUAUCAAAUGAUGGUCAUGACAAAUGCAUAUAUUUUUAAAACAUCUGUAUAGAUUAUUCUUAAUACAAUAUAUGGCGCAAUACGUAGUCACUGUUAAAAUUCAAGCACAGAAGAAAACAAGCAAAACAAAUAUAUGUUGUUAGAAGUUAGGAUACAGUUACCCUUGGUCCAGUGAUGGUCAUUAGGAGGGAGCAUGAGGUUUGAAGGUGAGCGUUUCUGCUUCUCAAUCUGGGAAUCACUUAUAUGAGUGUGUUUCAUUAGUAAAAGUCAUCAAGCUGUACACUCAGAUAUGUUGACUUUAGAGCUAUGGAUAUAGAUGUAAAUUAUACUUCAAGAAAGAGACUUUUUAAAAUCCAAGUACAGAACAUUGUAGAACCGUGUAAAAUUGGUAUUUGGAAGUUUCUUCAGCAAGCACAUGGGAUUACAGCUCAUGCCUGUAAUCCCAGUACUUUGGGAGGCCCACACAGAAUGAUCACUUGAGCUCAGGAGUUUGAGAGCAGCCUAGGCAACAUAGCAAGACCUCGACUCUACAAAAAAUUUUUAAAUUUUUUUCUGGGCAUGGUGGUGCUUGCCUGGAGUCCCAGCUAUUAGGGAGGAUGAGGUGGGAGGAUCUCCUGAGCCCAGGAGUUUGAGACUGCAGUGAGCUGUGAUCACGCCACUGCACUCCAGCCUGGGCAACACAGACAGACCUUGUCUCAAAAAUAAAUUUUUUCUAAAAAAAGUUUCUUGUUUUUUUUUCUUCCCAUAUUUUUUAAAACAUAAAAUUGAAAUCUCGAGAAUAUAAUACAUAAAAUAGAGAAUAUAGAAAAUUAAAUCUUCUAAUAUUGUUCUGCAGAUUUGAUCUUUUUUCUCUAAUAAUAAAUCAAGGCCUCCGGGUAUAUUUGUUUGUAUAUGUACAGGAAAAGGUCUGUAAGGAUUUACUUUCAGCUGUUAAUUGCAGUGACUCUGGGGAAUUUCCACUUCUGCUUUGUACAGUUCCUUGUGUGAAUUUUUACAUCAUGUAUUACUUUUGUAGUUGGGGAAAAAGCAAUUAAAAGUUUGGAAAAAAAGAACCUCUAGCCAUUGUUAUAAUAAGAAGUUGGAAUCAAUAAAAAUAUCCACAAACGAAA